CUGGGCGACAUAACGAGACUCCGUCUCUAAAGAAAAAAAAAAGAAGUAAAGGGCAGAGCUCACAGAUGGCUUUUUUCUUCUGAUUGCCAAAGUAAUGUCUUUUCAUUGCAGAUAUUUUGGAAACUAAGAAAAGCACAAAGAUGAAAACUAAAAUCAGCUGUAACUGUAUUAUUCAGAGAUACCCUAAUGAGUAUUUUGAUUUAUAGCUUUCCUGUCUUUUUUAUGUGUACGUACAUAUACUGAAAAUCAGUGGGCUUGCUCUGCACGUUACUGUAUUGUAGCUUGCUUGUUUCAUUUCAUCAUGUAUAAGACAUUAGUAACAUAUUGGCAGGUAAGUGAUGAAGAAAAGGGGAUUAGAUGUCCUGGGAUCAGAUGAUGGGUCUGUCCUGCUGUGUGAUCGAGGACAAGUAGCUUAACAUCUCUAAGUCUCAGUUUUUUCAUUUGUGUAAUGUAAGCAACAUUGGGAACCUCGCAAGGGUUCAGUGAUAGUUCCUAUAAACUAUUAGCCUAGUUUGUAACUGUCCACUAUUAUCAAGGAGGUUUUUGGGUUUUUUUUUUUUGAGACGGAGUCUCGCACUGUCACCCCCCGGGCUGGAGUGCAGUGACGUGAUCUCAGCUCACUGCAACCUCUGCCUCCCAGGUUCAAGCGAUUCUCCUGCCUCAGCCUCCCAAGUAGCUGGGAUUACAGGCGCCCACCACCAAGCCCAGCUAAUUUUUUGUAUUUUUAGUAGAGACAAGGUUUCACUAUGUUGGCCAGGCUGGUCUCAAACUCCUGACCUCGUGAUCCACCUGCCCCGGCCUCCCAAAAUGCUGGGAUUAACAGGCGUGAGCCACUGCACCUGGCCAAGGAGGCUGUUUUUUGUACCUCUACAGCACUUAAUGGACACUGCAGUUGAAUGUGUGGAGGCUUGUUUACUAAAAGUCUGACACAGUCUGGUUAUAAAAAACAGUGUCUUCUGAGUGCUAUUUGAAAACCUGUCCACUAAUCAAAAGUGUCAUUUAUAGUAGGGAAUCAUUAAAAAAAAUACAUAAAUACAUACCCCCUUAAAUAGUUAAUAUUUGAAUUAAACUCAAAAUAUUAAUACACACUGAGUUGCCCGUAGUUUGAUGUAGGAUUGCAGGCUUUGAGUGCUGGGCCACUGGUUUCAGCUGCAUCUUGCACACCCUCCUUCAUAAAACAUAAUCUACCAUUGCUACUUUGAGUUUCUUUUGGGUGGGGUCAGAACUUAAAGGCGUAUGAACUGAUAUGCUUCAGGAGUUUUAAUUUGUUUUCAAUUUUAUACAGUAGUUUAGGACACCCCUCAUCUGCCAAGAACUUUUUUCUGUGACAUUCCUUUAUUGGAUUUUUCAAACUGUUCAGCUUAGUUUUUGUGGAUACUCUUUUUGUCAGUUUAUAUGAUAAUUAAAUUACUCAACACGACGAUAACAAGUACAACUGACAUCAAACAGAUGUGUGAACAAACAAUUGAUUCUUGACAAGCACUGAAUUCAGUGGUGUGCCAGUGUGCUAGGGAGUGGCCUAAAAUCUAGAUGUGGGCCUUGGUCAGUUUACGUUUGGAAUGGAGAAUCUUGAUUGACCCAGCAGUCCAUUUAAGUGGAGGUUGGCAAGGAAACUUGGCCUGAACUUCAUUUUCUGGUUUGAAGGCAAUGACAUGCUUUCAUUCUUUAAUCAGGAACAUGUGAACCGACUGGCAUUCUGUAUUCUGAAUUCCUCCUGGGACAUUAGUGAUGUGUUUUUUUGUAACUUAGGAAUUGUACCUAAUUUAUUUUUUAACCAAAUAGCAUAUCUUCUUGAGAUGGCUAGCUGAGAAAGAGUAUGACACAAGUGUGAUCAAGGAUCAGCAAAAUUAACUACCCAUGCAAAGAUUAAACCUGUUACCUUUACUUCCCUAAUGUGGUAUUUUAACUAGCUGAGCUAACCACCAAUGGAGUGAUGGUAUGGCCUUUCCUGUACUCAAUUCAGUAAUUGAACAGUUAUUUAUCGAACCCUCUCCAGAUGCCAGGCACCCUGCAGAAAGUAACAUUCUGAAAAGGAACAGCCAUGCCUGUAGCCCAAAAGUGAGUAGUUGUAUUAAUGGUCCAUUCCUUAUUAACAAAUUAAUUUCCUCAGGAGUUUAUUGGACCAGAUAUCAAAGUCCCACUGGAAUGUCUUAAGUGAGAGAGAGGAUAAAUCAAAGUUUUCCUUAUCCAGGCUUUUUGGAUGUCUUUUUCCUGAGCCUCCUCUUCCAAGCCUGUUUUGCUCUCAGUCAGGAUUUACCAGCACUCUGCAUGUGUAGGCACGCUCACCUGCUUCCUUCUGUAGUGGUAAUGACAACCUACAUUUGUAUUCUGCAGUUGAUAAAGCCUGUUCGUGGUACAAUACCUCAUUUGACCCUCCCAACAACUGUAGGGUAGAUGUUAUCUACAUGAAAUUGAGUCUCAGAGAGGGGAUCGAUUUGCUUAGUGGUAUAAUACCUGAACUCUGUCAGAAAUAUCCAGAUUUAAAUUUCAUAAUUGGAGGAGAGGGACCAAAGAGAAUCAUUUUGGAAGAAGUUCGGGAAAGAUACCAGCUGCAUGACAGGGUGCGUCUUUUGGGAGCUUUAGAACACAAGGAUGUUAGAAAUGUCUUAGUUCAAGGACAUAUUUUUCUGAAUACCUCCCUUACUGAAGCAUUCUGCAUGGCGAUCGUGGAAGCAGCCAGUUGUGGUUUACAGGUUGUAAGUACCAGAGUUGGUGGAAUUCCUGAGGUGCUUCCAGAAAACCUUAUUAUUUUAUGUGAGCCUUCAGUAAAAUCUUUGUGUGAAGGAUUGGAAAAGGCUAUUUUCCAACUGAAGUCAGGGACAUUGCCAGCUCCAGAAAACAUCCAUAACAUAGUAAAGACUUUCUACACCUGGAGGAAUGUUGCAGAAAGAACUGAAAAGGUAUAUGACCGGGUAUCAGUGGAAGCUGUGUUGCCAAUGGACAAACGACUGGACAGACUUAUUUCUCACUGCGGCCCAGUAACAGGCUACAUCUUUGCUUUGUUGGCAGUUUUCAACUUCCUCUUCCUCAUUUUCUUGAGAUGGAUGACUCCAGAUUCUAUCAUUGAUGUUGCAAUAGAUGCCACUGGGCCACGGGGUGCCUGGACUAAUAACUAUUCUCACAGUAAAAGAGGGGGUGAGAAUAAUGAGAUAUCUGAAACCAGGUAGAAGGAAGCCUAGAUUGUAAGAUUUUAAACAUUUGUAAUAGUUCUAUAAAGACUAUGGAAAAUAACCUUGCUUUUGGGGGGUUUUUGUUUUUUUAGAGUUAAUUUAGUAAGUUAUGCUACCUCUAUAUCAUUCAAUAUUUUCUGUUGAGGAAAGAUAAAAAUGUAUGCAAUUCCUGAGUGUAGAAACUUCUUGCACUUAUUUAAAAUUUAGGAGAGAACAUUUAAGCCACUCAGGUAUGCAAUUUUUCAGACUACUGAAAUCCCUGUAGCAGAGAUGUUUUAACAUUAUAUUUUGAGAGCUUUGGGUGCUGAAGGGCCAAACGUUUUCUGGGCAUUUUUUGGCCAGUUUUUAAUGUAACACCAUUAGACACUCACCAGAUGUUUACAAGUUUUCUUUAGGGGAACUACAACAAUUAUAUGAACUGUUUUAUAUCAUGUUCAUAUACAUUUAUUAGGAAUCUAAAUCAUGUCUUUGAACAUUUAUUAGGUUCACUCAGUAGGUGUUACAUGUAAUUAACAGGUUCCUUGAGUAAGAUAGUCCAUCAGUUACCAGCACAUUUUGAACCCCUGCUCUGUGUAGAAUGUUGAACUAGAUGCUUCCCGCCAUUAAGGACCAGGGGUGCAUUCACUCUUUGUUUACCAUUCAAAUGGCUUACUUCAUCAUAAUUGUGGUUGAUAUGAGAUCAAUAUCCAACAUGCCAAAAAUGCUCAUGCCAGUUAAUGCCAGGAAAAAAAUCACCGACACACUACUAGUACUUUGUUCCUGUUGUAUGCAUUCUCCUAGGUAGAGCCUCCAUCUUCAGUUGUGUUUGUGAAGGUAUUUUUUGCUUUUUAAAUACUGGGGACCGAUAUCACUGUUGAUAGUGCAGAGAAACCCUCCACAUUUUUCAGUGCAUAAUUGAGUUUUCUAUAAAUGCCUUCGUGUUUUCUGAGCAGAAUGUACGAGGUGUGCCAUCCCAAAACCAGCUGCUACCCUGUCCUUUUAAUGUAAGUCACUCCCCUUCACUGUGGCCUCGCUGAUGUCUGAUAAGUAUUGUCAGUGUGCAAAAGGCUUUACUUCAGAAUGGUUUAUUUAUAGCAAACUAAGUUGAAAAUUUUAGAAACAGUCUUUGUGGGUGGAUGUUAUUAACUGUCAUUGUUGUUGCCCAGAGCCAUGGGUUUUUUAACCCCAAAUUAUCCACAUGGUGUGUAUUAUGAAUUCUUUGAACUCUUAAGGUUUUUGUGAGAAAAGGACUGUGAAUUCAAAACAAUAAGGCACUUGUGGGUGCACUACAUAGAUUCUGACAGUGUUGUGAUUCUGUAUAGGAUUUUUAAAAAUGACAACAUUCACAAAAUUUAUUACUUUUUAAAAAAUAACAUGCCUAUUAACUGGUUGCACUGAUAUAAAAGAAAUAUAUUUGUGUUUUGUUUGUACUAAAAUGCAAAAGCAAGAGUGCAAUUUUUAAAAUCUAGAAGUUAGGGGUUUUGUUGGAGAAAAAUGGACUGAUCUUUAAACUAUUCAGUCUUACUGGGAUUUUUAUGCAUAGAAACUCACAUAUAAACAUGAAAUAAACAGUGCCAGUAUUCAUAGGAAAGUGAGAAACUGUAAUAUUUGGCCAUUAUUCUAUUCAACAGGUUUUAGAGGCAUGCCACCAUUUUUUCCUUAUAUUUUUGCUUAAUUUUUUUAAAUUGUCAUUUAAUUCUUAAACUGUCAUUUAUUUGAGAUGGAAAUAAGAUCUAAAGUUAGUUGCCUUUGCCUGUAAAACAUGUGAUUUGCAAAUUAUUAUUUUUCUUUUUUUUAACAAAUGGAAGUAAAUUUGUUUCACGUAAAUCUUAAUUUUCAACCUUUCUGGAUACCUUAAUUGUAACUGUCAGUUUGCACUGGUCGGUAUAUGGAAACACAUUGCUCUACCCUGCUACUUAGUUGAUUUUAAAGUGAAUUUACAGUGAUGAGAAAUUUGUGAAAAAUAUAUUGUAUUUCUUUUGAUGUUUCAAAAGGUUGCCUAUGAAAAACUGAUUUGUUAAAACAUGCUACAUGUCCAAAAAUAAAGACCAGAAUGACAUUUUGAUAAUUUUC